CUACUCAUGGCGCCUGCCCUGGUUGGCGAUGUGUUACCAACGUCUGGCCUGUCCCAGCCCAAGGCUCCGCGUGGCGACCAGGCCCAGCACUGGGAGGCUGUGCAGAGCGUGGCGUUUACUGCUUAUUGCUACUCUGCAGAGGUUGGCAACAUCUGACCCGCUCUACUGGCAGGAAACAGGCUCGGGGGCAUUGGGAAAACGAUCAAGGCCACUUGGCUGGACACUGGCGGAGCCUCGCACUCAAACCUGUCGGGCCUCAACUCCGUGCCAGGCCAACAAGUUGCCCUGGGCAGUUCAAGCUGGGGAUAAGGGGGAUGGGGAGCAGGAAGACAGCAGCAAGGAUGCGAUCCCGAAGGAACUUUCCUCCUCAGACUGCUCCAUGUCCAUGUGGGGCAGGUCGCUGAAGAGUUCGAAACCGUGCUCAGCACCGCGUUUGGGGCAUGUGAGACCGAGAGGCUUUGGGAAACUGACGCCGCUGUGAGAACGAGUUUAGCGGAGUCUAUGGACGCUGCGAGCUUGUGGCCACAAGAGGGCGCCCCGGAGCACGGCCCAGUCCCCGCCCCCGCUGGAUGGGGCCCGGCCUCUUCCCAGCGUUCCUCCUCCGGCCCCAGGUCACCGCCAGCACGCGCCUGCUUCCCGUCUGCGCGAGUCCACGCAGCUCCCCAGGUCUGGGGCACUCCAAGGAAGCAGCAGCCCCUGCCCCUAUUGGGGAGCUGGCCCCUGGCAGCUUCCUGGCGGCUGUGGUGGAUGCCUUGGAGCUGGGCCCCCCGGUUGUGAUCAGUCCAUCACUGAGUGGCAUGUACUCCCUGCCCUUCCUCACGGCCCCUGGCUCCCAGCUCCCGGGCUUUGUGCCAGUGGCCCCCAUCUGCACUGACAAAAUCAAUGCUGCCAACUAUGCCAGUGUGAAGACUCCAGCUCUGAUUGUAUAUGGAGACCAGGACCCCAUGGGUCAGACCAGCUUUGAGCACCUGAAGCAGCUGCCCAACCACCGGGUGCUGAUCAUGAAGGGGGCGGGGCACCCCUGUUACCUGGACAAACCAGAGGAGUGGCAUACAGGGCUGCUGGACUUCCUGCAGGGGCUCCAGUGAAGCCCAGCACUGCUGCAGGGGGUGGGCUGCCUGCCUGCUCUGAGCUCUCUCUUGCACGCUCUCUCUUCUCUCCCAGGCUCUGGCUCAUGCACAUGCAACAGGUGCGUCUGUCUAUAUGUCUGGGUUCUUGUCUUUUGUGGUCUGUUUGUCUUUUCUACCUCUUUCUCUUGCAGUGAUAGACUGAGGGGGUAAAAUCAAGAGAAAAAACUCUCAGGAAUCAAGGAACAUAAUCCUGUGGAGGGUAAUCCAUUACAUGAGCUUCUCCUGUUCUUCCACUUUCCUGCCUGGCUUUCACUCCUUCCCCUGCUCUGCCCAGCCUUUCCCUCCCACCCACUCCUCCUUCUGCAAAUGCCCUGAAGGCCAGCCCUUACCCCAACACCCACUUCCCCACCUCCUUAGGCCCCAGAUACAUACAUGCCCACAUGCACGCUUACAUGUUUAGAGCCAUCCUUGUUUCCAAAUAUGACCCUUCGCUUGAGGGCAACUGCAUAGGUACAUCUAACUCUGGACUGGCAUGCACAUUGUCAUGUGCAGCUUUGCAUAUACACACAUGCAUACAUGAGCCUCCACACAAGCACUUGCACACAUGUGGACUCCUAACCAUGCUAACCUCACUGGCUGGGAAGGUGGGGACCCCAUGGGCCAGCCCUUGCAGGAGGCCCUUUUGCAAGGCUUAGGGUGUGGCCAGCCCUGAAAGCUACUUGGACACAGGUUUCAGCUGGCCCCAGCCCAGAAGUGACCCCCAGAAAGGGAGGGCCACCGCUUUGCCCCCUGCUUUUACCCUUCCUUCUGGGUGCUCUACACCUCAGGUUACCAGGCCUGAGGCAUCUCAGCCAAGCUUGUUUCCUGCUCUGAGGCUUGUGGGGUGGGAGCCAGAGUGGAGGUCGGUGAAAUAAAGUGAUGCAAUUAGACCCCA